GCAGACGCCCAGCGGCGCCAAGAACCCGGCCAAGCUGACUUGGCGACUCCUCGCAGCCCCUGCUCUGGCACGCCACACCUCAGACGAGGCUUUGAAAGUAGGGCGCAGCCUGAGAGGCCGGCCGGACCCCGAGUGCUGUAGGCGGGCUGGGAGAUGGGGGCCGCCGCCACCCACAUUCCCACACGCACCCGGCGCCGGCGCCUCACGCCGUGUUAGCUCGCGGCGCCAAGCCCGGAGGGUCCCGCCUGAGGAAGAAAGGUCGUCGCCCGCAGCCCAGCUGGGGCUGGAGGCGCGACCCGGGGUCUCCUCGCCCGCACGCGGAAGAAAAUGGGCGCUGUGGCCUCAGUUUCCCUCUUUUGUUAAAUACAAGUAAGGAACACAGGCAACAUGUUCUACACACAUGUGCUUAUGAGUAAACGAGGGCCAUUGGCCAAAAUAUGGCUUGCAGCUCACUGGGAGAAGAAACUCACAAAGGCCCAUGUAUUUGAAUGUAAUCUAGAGAUAACCAUUGAAAAAAUUCUUUCACCCAAGGUGAAAAUAGCACUUCGAACUUCAGGACACCUUCUUUUGGGAGUUGUUCGAAUCUAUAACAGGAAGGCAAAAUAUCUUUUGGCAGAUUGCAGUGAAGCAUUUCUUAAAAUGAAGAUGACAUUUUGCCCAGGACUGGUUGACCUUCCAAAAGAGAAUUUUGAAGCAUCUUACAAUGCUAUCACAUUGCCAGAAGAAUUUCAUGAUUUUGACACCCAAAAUAUGAAUGCUAUUGAUGUUUCAGAACACUUUACUCAGAACCAAAGCAGACCAGAAGAAAUCACUCUUAGAGAAAAUUUUGACAAUGAUCUAAUUUUCCAAGCUGAGAGCUUUGGGGAGGAAUCUGAAAUUCUCAGAAGACAUAGCUUCUUUGAUGACAACAUAUUACUGAAUUCCAGUGGUCCUUUAAUUGAACAUAGUUCUGGAAGCCUCACUGGAGAACGAUCUCUAUUCUAUGACAGUGGAGAUGGGUUUGGAGAUGAAGGAGCUGCAGGAGAAAUGAUUGACAAUCUAUUGCAAGAUGAUCAGAAUAUCCUGUUAGAAGACAUGCAUUUGAACAGAGAAAUUUCCCUGCCUUCUGAGCCUCCCAAUAGUUUAGCAGUUGAACCAGAUAACUCAGAGUGUAUAUGUGUACCUGAAAAUGAAAAAAUGAAUGAAACAAUAUUAUUAUCAACUGAAGAGGAAGGAUUUACCCUUGAUCCAAUUGAUAUUUCAGACAUUGCUGAGAAAAGGAAAGGCAAAAAGAGGAGAUUGCUCAUAGAUCCUAUCAAGGAGCUCAGUAGCAAAGUUAUACAUAAACAGCUUACUUCCUUUGCGGACACACUCAUGGUUUUGGAACUUGCACCUCCUACCCAAAGAUUGAUGAUGUGGAAGAAGAGGGGAGGAGUGCAUACACUUCUGUCAACUGCUGCCCAGGAUUUGAUUCAUGCUGAACUGAAAAUGGUAACGGUUCCUACCCUUCUACAUUUGUUUACAAAAUGCUUUCUGUCCUCUGGCUUUAAACUUGGAAGAAAAAUGAUACAGAAGGAGUCAGUAAGGGAAGAAGUGGGAAACCAAAAUAUAGUAGAGACAUCCAUGAUGCAAGAGCCAAAUUACCAGCAAGAGUUAAGUAAACCCCAAACUUGGAAGGAUGUGAUUGGUGGAUCUCAGCAUAGCUCUCAUGAGGAUACCAAUAAAAAUAUUAACUCUGAGCAGGAUAUUGUUGAAAUGGUGUCUUUAGCUGCUGAGGAAUCAUCUUUAAUGAAUGACUUAUUUGCACAAGAAAUUGAAUAUAGUCCAGUUGAAUUGGAGUCAUUGAGCAAUGAAGAAAAUAUUGAGACAGAGAGAUGGAAUGGAAGAAUACUUCAGAUGUUAAAUCGUUUACGGGAAUCUAACAAGAUGGGAAUGCAGUCCUUUAGUCUGAUGAAGCUCUGUAGAAAUAGUGACCGAAAACAAGCAGCUGCCAAAUUUUAUAGCUUUCUUGUCCUAAAGAAACAGCUGGCUAUUGAGCUGAGCCAGAGUGCUCCCUAUGCAGAUAUUAUAGCUACGAUGGGACCAAUGUUUUAUAACAUAUGAAGGAAACCCAGACAUACAGAUUUAUGGCAUCACUGGAAUUUCUGUGUAGAUUGUUCAAUUUAAUGCAGAAGCCAUCUGGAAGCAGCUGAAGGUCUGAUCCAUUUCAUAGAUAGGCUGACCUACUUCCUCUCUGUAGUUCAGAAUAAUCAUAGCUAGAAUUGGAAACCUACAUGCUUACAAAGAAAUACUUUAAAUUCUGUUUUGUUUUUUUUUGUUGUUUUUUUAAGGACAAAGGUCUCACUAUAUUGCCCAGGCUGGACUUGAACUCUGGGUUCAAGUGAUUCUCCUGCCUCAGCCUCCUGAAUAGCUGGGACUACAGGCACAUGCCACCAUACCUGGCUCAGAAAUACUUAAUUAUAGCUAAGUAAUUAUUUUUAACUUAGCUGAUUUGAAUAUAUAGCAUUUAUCAUUUCCCUGAUUUGAAUGUUGCACUUAGCAUACAUUUAGCAUGCAUUUUUAAAAUGCUGUAUGUUUUUGACAGACAUUCAAAGAUGUUUCUUAAAAGGCUAUUUUACAUUGGAGUAUUUACUUGAAUUUUAUGGGGUUAAUGAAAACAUCAUUAUUUCUACACAGACUAUUUGGUUGCAACGUAUAUCAUACUUGAUUUGACAUAAUGCCAUGGUUUUUAAUCCAAUAUUUUAAUUGAAGAGUUACAAAGCUCAUCUUUGCUUUAAAUUGCCUGAGUGGGUUUUAGUCUAUUUAUAGGUCACUUAACUUUUUUAUUUACUAUUUAAUGAUUAUUAUAAUCACCAUUAAUGUGUCAGCAAAACUAAAUCUGCUUCUUAUGUUUAAAAAAAUUAGCAGACACUUGUUCCUCAUGUUGUUUGCAGCUACGGUCUGAGUAAAGAUCACCAAAAUAAAUGUUCUUUUGUUUGGUGUUUACUGAACAUUUUUGACAUUAAAACUGUUGUUUUCCUUUUUUCUUAAUUGAAGUUUGAGUUAGGACAUUUUCAUAUGAUGCUCUGUGAGCUCCAUCAUACACUGUCAAAUGAAGCCUAUGGUACUCAUUAAAAUGUUGUUAUAUCUGGAAUUAUGCUGCAAACAACAAAUUCUAAAUAGCCUCUCUAAAUGUGUUAACUAUAAAUUUUAAAUGGCAAAAUUGCCUUUUUAAAAUUUCUUUUAUUUUUUAAAUUAACAUACAGAAAAUUUGACUUCUUAAUUUUGGUGCACAGUUCUGUGAAUUUUAACAUAUUUGUAGAGUCCUGUAACCAUCUCCACAAUUAGGAUUCCAGCAGUAACAUCACCCUAAAAAAUUCUGUUAUCCCUUUGUAGUAACCCCCUUCCCCCAUAUAACAUCUGGCAACCACUCUUCUCCAUGACUACACUUUUGUCUUUUUGAAAAUGUCACACAGAUGGAAUCAUAUAGCAUGUAAGCUUUCGAUACGGGCUUCUUUCACUCAUAAAUGUCUUUGAGACUUA